AUGUCUGGCCACGAAGGUGGCAAGAAAAAGUCCCUAAAACAGCCCAAGAAACAGGCCAAGAAGACGGAUGGAGAUAAGGCUUUCAAGCAGAAACAAAAAGAGGAGCAGAAGAAAUUUGAGGGGCUAAAAGCAAAGGCCAUGGGGAAGGGACCCCUCACCACAGGUGGAAUUAAGAAAUCUGGCAAUUGGCUGGGCAUGGUUGCUCACACCUGUAUCUACUGUGUACACAGAAUUGAAGUGGAUCUUCCCCUCAACAACUCAUUCUCCCAGCUUUCUCCCAAGGACAUCUCCUAG